GGACCUUGCACCAAGCAGCCAUAGCUGAGAGUUGGAGAAUCAAGUCUCUCUUCAGUUAAGUGUCUAUAAUUACCUAAUUUGUUCUUUCUGCAUGCCUGGGAGAGAGGAUGGUAGGCAGAGGGGGCUUGCUGUUUUUAGGAAUUUUCCUGGCUGGAUGAAGGGGUACUUCUUAUCUAUCAGAGGGAGCUAUUACAUUAGCUCAGGGUCUUACUCAGUAUCCUAGUGCUGACGAAUUAAAAUUAGAAACUUCAGAACUUGGGCUGCAACUUUUGGCAAACUUAGGGAGCUGCAUUCUGUUCCUGGUUCUGCCAUGCACUAGCAUGGAACUGUGGGCACAUUGUGUAACCUCUCUGAGUCUGGUGUUUGUUCCUAGUUUUCCAUUUUAAUGGAGUAUCUGUAUUGCCUUCCUCGGGGUGGUGCUAUUCAGUGAGGCAAUGCAAGGGGGAGUUCAAUGAAACUGGGACAUCUAUACACAUGUGAGGGAGCCUGGGCUGGAAGAGGCAGCAAAAGGGAAAAUCAGAAGAGUGGACACUGGCAAGAGGAGGGCAGCCUUUUUCCCAGCUUCCUUGCACCAUGGACAGCUCCCAUUAAGCCACCUCUCCAUCCUGGGGCCAGGACUCUUAUGCCCCAUUCCUGUCAAAUUGAGAUUUCAUCCACCAUUCUCCAAGGACAGUGAAGUUAUACCCUAGUUCCAGUGUUGGGAUCAGUGGCCCCUCUGGACAUGCCUCUCCUGGAAGGUUCUGUGGGGGUGGAGGAUCUUGUCCUCCUGGAACCCUUGGUGGAGGAGUCACUGCUCAAGAAUCUUCAGCUUCGCUAUGAAAACAAGGAGAUUUAUACCUACAUUGGGAAUGUGGUGAUCUCAGUGAAUCCCUAUCAACAGCUUCCCAUCUAUGGGCCAGAGUUCAUUGCCAAAUAUCAAGACUAUACUUUCUAUGAGCUGAAGCCCCAUAUCUACGCAUUGGCAAAUGUGGCGUACCAGUCACUGAGGGACAGGGACCGAGACCAGUGUAUCCUCAUCACAGGCGAGAGUGGAUCAGGGAAGACUGAGGCCAGCAAGCUGGUGAUGUCUUAUGUGGCUGCCGUCUGUGGGAAAGGAGAGCAGGUGAACUCUGUGAAGGAGCAGCUGCUACAGUCUAACCCAGUGCUGGAGGCUUUUGGCAAUGCCAAGACCAUUCGCAACAACAAUUCCUCCCGAUUUGGAAAAUACAUGGAUAUUGAAUUUGACUUCAAGGGAUCCCCCCUCGGUGGUGUCAUCACAAACUAUCUGCUUGAGAAAUCCCGAUUAGUGAAGCAGCUCAAAGGAGAAAGGAACUUCCACAUCUUCUAUCAGCUGCUGGCUGGAGCAGAUGAACAGCUGCUGAAGGCCCUGAAGCUUGAGCGGGAUACAACUGGCUAUGCCUAUCUGAAUCAUGAAGUAUCCAGAGUGGAUGGCAUGGACGACGCCUCCAGCUUCAGGGCUGUACAGAGUGCAAUGGCAGUGAUUGGGUUCUCGGAGGAGGAGAUUCGACAAGUGCUAGAGGUGACAUCCAUGGUGCUAAAGCUGGGGAACGUGUUGGUGGCUGAUGAGUUCCAGGCCAGUGGGAUACCAGCAAGUGGCAUCCGUGAUGGGAGAGGUGUUCGGGAGAUUGGGGAGAUGGUGGGCUUGAAUUCAGAAGAAGUAGAGAGAGCUUUGUGCUCGAGGACCAUGGAAACAGCCAAGGAAAAGGUGGUCACUGCACUGAAUGUUAUGCAGGCUCAGUAUGCUCGGGACGCCCUGGCUAAGAACAUCUACAGCCGCCUCUUUGACUGGAUAGUGAAUCGAAUCAAUGAGAGCAUCAAGGUGGGCAUCGGGGAAAAGAAGAAGGUAAUGGGAGUCCUUGAUAUCUACGGUUUUGAGAUAUUAGAGGAUAAUAGCUUUGAGCAAUUUGUGAUCAACUACUGCAAUGAGAAGCUGCAGCAGGUGUUCAUAGAGAUGACCCUGAAAGAAGAGCAAGAGGAAUAUAAGAGAGAAGGCAUACCGUGGACAAAGGUGGACUACUUUGAUAAUGGCAUCAUUUGUAAGCUCAUUGAGCAUAAUCAGCGAGGUAUCCUGGCCAUGUUGGAUGAGGAGUGCCUGCGGCCUGGGGUGGUCAGUGACUCCACUUUCCUAGCAAAGCUGAACCAGCUCUUCUCCAAGCAUGGCCACUACGAGAGCAAAGUCACCCAGAAUGCCCAGCGUCAGUAUGACCACACCAUGGGCCUCAGCUGCUUCCGCAUCUGCCACUAUGCGGGCAAGGUGACAUACAACGUGACCAGCUUUAUUGACAAGAAUAAUGACCUACUCUUCCGAGACCUGUUGCAGGCCAUGUGGAAGGCCCAGCACCCCCUCCUUCGGUCCUUGUUUCCUGAGGGCAAUCCUAAGCAGGCAUCUCUCAAACGCCCCCCGACUGCUGGGGCCCAGUUCAAGAGUUCUGUGGCCAUCCUCAUGAAGAAUCUGUAUUCCAAGAGCCCCAACUACAUCAGGUGCAUAAAGCCCAAUGAGCAUCAGCAGCGAGGUCAGUUCUCUUCAGACCUGGUGGCAACCCAGGCUCGGUACCUGGGACUGCUGGAGAACGUACGGGUGCGACGGGCAGGCUAUGCCCACCGCCAGGGUUAUGGGCCCUUCCUGGAAAGGUACCGAUUGCUGAGCCGGAGCACCUGGCCUCACUGGAAUGGGGGAGACCGGGAAGGUGUUGAGAAGGUCCUGGGGGAGCUGAGCAUGUCCUCGGGGGAGCUGGCCUUUGGCAAGACAAAGAUCUUCAUUAGAAGCCCCAAGACUCUUUUCUACCUCGAAGAACAGAGGCGCCUGAGACUCCAGCAGCUGGCCACACUCAUACAGAAGAUUUACCGAGGCUGGCGCUGCCGCACCCACUACCAACUGAUGCGAAAGAGUCAGAUCCUCAUCUCCUCUUGGUUUCGGGGAAACAUGCAAAAGAAAUGCUAUGGGAAGAUAAAGGCAUCCGUGUUAUUGAUCCAGGCUUUUGUGAGAGGGUGGAAGGCCCGAAAGAAUUAUCGCAAAUAUUUCCGGUCAGAGGCUGCCCUCACCUUGGCAGAUUUCAUCUACAAGAGCAUGGUACAGAAAUUCCUACUGGGGCUGAAGAACAAUUUGCCAUCCACAAACGUCUUAGACAAGACAUGGCCAGCCGCCCCCUACAAGUGCCUCAGCACAGCAAAUCAGGAGCUGCAGCAGCUCUUCUACCAGUGGAAGUGCAAGAGGUUCCGGGAUCAGCUGUCCCCGAAGCAGGUAGAGAUCCUGAGGGAAAAGCUCUGUGCCAGUGAACUGUUCAAGGGCAAGAAGGCUUCAUAUCCCCAGAGUGUCCCCAUUCCAUUCUGUGGUGACUACAUUGGGCUGCAAGGGAACCCCAAGCUGCAGAAGCUGAAAGGCGGGGAGGAGGGGCCUGUUCUGAUGGCAGAGGCCGUGAAGAAGGUCAAUCGUGGCAAUGGCAAGACUUCUUCUCGGAUUCUCCUCCUGACCAAGGGCCAUGUGAUUCUCACAGACACCAAGAAGUCCCAGGCCAAAAUUGUCAUUGGGCUAGACAAUGUGGCUGGGGUGUCAGUCACCAGCCUCAAGGAUGGGCUCUUUAGCUUGCAUCUGAGUGAGAUGUCAUCGGUGGGCUCCAAGGGGGACUUCCUGCUGGUCAGCGAGCAUGUGAUUGAACUGCUGACCAAAAUGUACCGGGCUGUGCUGGAUGCCACGCAGAGGCAGCUUACAGUCACCGUGACUGAGAAGUUCUCAGUGAGGUUCAAGGAGAACAGUGUGGCUGUCAAGGUCGUCCAGGGCCCUGCAGGUGGUGACAACAGCAAGCUACGCUACAAAAAAAAGGGGAGUCAUUGCUUGGAGGUGACUGUGCAGUGAGGAGGGGGCACCAUGCAGAGAUGGCAGUUGCUUCCUCCUGAACCAGCACUAAUCCCCCUCUGCCCUCCUGUGUGGGAGGAUCUCUAACCCCUCUGAUCGUGGCGCAUGGCUUGGGGAUUAAACUACCCUUGAAGAGGACCCUUGUCCCAAACCCUUCUUGUUCUCUCCUCCAAAAGUAGCUUCCUCCAACCCGCAGCCUCUCUGCACACUAAUAAAACAUGUGGCUUGGAAAGGUUCA